GAGAAGAACCCAGCAAAAUGGGGAUCUCCACAGUCAUCCUUGAAAUGUGUCUUUUAUGGGGACAAGUUCUAUCUACAGGUGGGUGGAUCCCAAGGACUACAGACUACGCUUCACUGAUUCCCUCGGAGGUGCCCUUGGAUCCAACUGUAGCAGAAGGUUCUCCAUUUCCCUCGGAGUCGACCCUGGAGUCAACUGUAGCAGAAGGUUCUCCGAUUUCCUUGGAGUCAACCCUGGAGUCAACCGUAGCAGAAGGUUCUCUGAUUCCCUCAGAGUCAACCCUGGAGUCAACUGUAGCAGAAGGAUCUGAUUCUGGUUUGGCCCUGAGGCUGGUGAAUGGAGAUGGCAGGUGUCAGGGCCGAGUGGAGAUCCUAUACCGAGGCUCCUGGGGCACCGUGUGUGAUGACAGCUGGGACACCAAUGAUGCCAACGUGGUCUGUAGGCAGCUGGGUUGUGGCUGGGCCAUGUCAGCUCCAGGAAAUGCCUGGUUUGGCCAGGGCUCAGGACCCAUUGCCCUGGAUGAUGUGCGCUGCUCAGGACACGAAUCCUACCUGUGGAGCUGCCCCCACAAUGGCUGGCUCUCCCAUAACUGUGGCCAUGGUGAAGAUGCUGGUGUUAUCUGCUCAGCUGCCCAGCCUCAGUCAACACUCAGGCCAGAAAGUUGGCCUGUCAGGAUAUCACCACCUGUACCCACAGAAGGAUCUGAAUCCAGUUUGGCCCUGAGGCUGGUGAAUGGAGGCGACAGGUGUCGAGGCCGAGUGGAGGUCCUAUACCGAGGCUCCUGGGGCACCGUGUGUGAUGACUACUGGGACACCAAUGAUGCCAAUGUGGUCUGCAGGCAGCUGGGCUGUGGCUGGGCCAUGUCAGCCCCAGGAAAUGCCCAGUUUGGCCAGGGCUCAGGACCCAUUGUCCUGGAUGAUGUGCGCUGCUCAGGACAUGAGUCCUACCUGUGGAGCUGCCCCCACAAUGGCUGGCUCACCCACAACUGUGGCCAUAGUGAAGACGCUGGUGUCAUCUGCUCAGCUCCCCAGUCCCGGCCGACACCCAGCCCAGAUACUUGGCCGACCUCACAUGCAUCAACAGCAGGACCUGAAUCCAGUUUGGCCCUGAGGCUGGUGAAUGGAGGUGACAGGUGUCAGGGCCGAGUGGAGGUCCUAUACCGAGGCUCCUGGGGCACCGUGUGUGAUGAUAGCUGGGACACCAGUGACGCCAAUGUGGUCUGCCGGCAGCUGGGCUGUGGCUGGGCCACGUCAGCCCCAGGAAAUGCCCGGUUUGGCCAGGGUUCAGGACCCAUUGUCCUGGAUGACGUGCGCUGCUCAGGCUAUGAGUCCUACCUGUGGAGCUGCCCCCACAAUGGCUGGCUCUCCCAUAACUGUCAGCACAGUGAAGACGCUGGUGUCAUCUGCUCAGCUGCCCACUCCUGGUCGACGCCCAGUCCAGACACGUUGCCGACCAUCACCUUACCUGCAUCGACAGUAGGAUCUGAAUCCAGUUUGGCCCUGAGGCUGGUGAAUGGAGGUGACAGGUGUCAGGGCCGAGUGGAGGUCCUAUACCGAGGCUCCUGGGGCACCGUGUGUGAUGACAGCUGGGACACCAAUGAUGCCAAUGUGGUCUGCAGGCAGCUGGGCUGUGGCUGGGCCAUGUUGGCCCCAGGAAAUGCCCGGUUUGGUCAGGGCUCAGGACCCAUUGUCCUGGAUGACGUGCGCUGCUCAGGGAAUGAGUCCUACUUGUGGAGCUGCCCCCACAAUGGCUGGCUCUCCCAUAACUGUGGCCAUAGUGAAGACGCUGGUGUCAUCUGCUCAGGACCUGAAUCCAGUUUGGCCCUGAGGCUGGUGAAUGGAGGUGACAGGUGUCAGGGCCGAGUGGAGGUCCUAUACCGAGGCUCUUGGGGCACCGUGUGUGAUGACAGCUGGGACACCAAUGAUGCCAAUGUGGUCUGCAGGCAGCUGGGCUGUGGCUGGGCCACGUCAGCCCCAGGAAAUGCCCGGUUUGGUCAGGGCUCAGGACCCAUUGUCCUGGAUGAUGUGCGCUGCUCAGGACAUGAGUCCUACCUGUGGAGCUGCCCCAACAAUGGCUGGCUCUCCCACAACUGUGGCCAUCAUGAAGAUGCUGGUGUCAUCUGCUCAGCUGCCCAGUCCCGGUCGACGCCCAGGCCAGACACGUUGUCGACCAUCACGUUACCUCCAUCGACAGUAGGAUCUGAAUCCAGUUUGACCCUGAGGCUGGUGAAUGGAAGUGACAGGUGUCAGGGCCGAGUAGAGGUCCUAUACCGAGGCUCCUGGGGCACCGUGUGUGAUGACAGCUGGGAUACCAAUGAUGCCAAUGUGGUCUGCAGGCAGCUGGGCUGUGGCUGGGCCACGUCGGCCCCAGGAAAUGCCCGGUUUGGCCAGGGCUCAGGACCCAUUGUUCUGGAUGAUGUGCGCUGCUCAGGACACGAGUCCUACCUGUGGAGCUGCCCCCACAAUGGCUGGCUCUCCCACAACUGUGGCCAUCAUGAAGAUGCUGGUGUCAUCUGCUCAGUUUCCCAGUCCCGGCCGACACCCAGUCCAGAUACUUGGCCGACCUCACAUGCAUCAACAGCAGGACCUGAAUCCAGUUUGGCCCUGAGGCUGGUGAAUGGAGGUGACAGGUGUCAGGGCCGAGUGGAGGUCCUAUACCGAGGCUCCUGGGGCACCGUGUGUGAUGAUAGCUGGGACACCAGUGACGCCAAUGUGGUCUGCCGGCAGCUGGGCUGUGGCUGGGCCACGUCAGCCCCAGGAAAUGCCCGGUUUGGCCAGGGUUCAGGACCCAUUGUCCUGGAUGACGUGCGCUGCUCAGGCUAUGAGUCCUACCUGUGGAGCUGCCCCCACAAUGGCUGGCUCUCCCAUAACUGUCAGCACAGUGAAGACGCUGGUGUCAUCUGCUCAGCUGCCCACUCCUGGUCGACGCCCAGUCCAGACACAUUGCCGACCAUCACCUUGCCUGCAUCGACAGUAGGAUCUGAAUCCAGUUUGGCCCUGAGGCUGGUGAAUGGAGGUGACAGGUGUCAGGGCCGAGUGGAGGUCCUAUACCAAGGCUCCUGGGGCACCGUGUGCGAUGACAGCUGGGACACCAAUGAUGCCAAUGUCGUCUGCAGGCAACUGGGCUGUGGCUGGGCCAUGUCAGCCCCAGGAAAUGCCCGGUUUGGUCAGGGCUCAGGACCCAUUGUCCUGGAUGAUGUGCGCUGCUCAGGACACGAGUCUUACCUGUGGAGCUGCCCCCACAAUGGCUGGCUCUCCCACAACUGUGGCCAUAGUGAAGACGCUGGUGUCAUCUGCUCAGCUUCCCAGUCCCGGCCAACACCUAGUCCAGACACUUGGCCAACCUCACAUGCAUCAACAGCAGGAUCUGAAUCCAGUUUGGCCCUGAGGCUGGUGAAUGGAGGUGACAGGUGUCAGGGCCGAGUGGAGGUCCUAUACCGAGGCUCCUGGGGCACCGUGUGUGAUGACUACUGGGACACCAAUGAUGCCAAUGUGGUUUGCAGGCAGCUGGGCUGUGGCUGGGCCAUGUCAGCCCCAGGAAAUGCCCGGUUUGGCCAGGGUUCAGGACCCAUUGUCCUGGAUGAUGUGCGCUGCUCAGGACAUGAGUCCUAUCUGUGGAGCUGCCCCCACAAUGGCUGGCUCUCCCACAACUGUGGCCAUCAUGAAGACGCUGGUGUCAUCUGCUCAGCUUCCCAGUCCCAGCCGACACCCAGCCCAGACACUUGGCCAACCUCACAUGCAUCAACAGCAGGAUCUGAAUCCAGUUUGGCCCUGAGGCUGGUGAAUGGAGGUGACAGGUGUCAGGGCCGAGUGGAGGUCCUAUACCGAGGCUCCUGGGGCACCGUGUGUGAUGACUACUGGGACACCAAUGAUGCCAAUGUGGUUUGCAGGCAGCUGGGCUGUGGCUGGGCCACGUCAGCCCCAGGAAAUGCCCGGUUUGGCCAGGGUUCAGGACCCAUUGUCCUGGAUGAUGUGCGCUGCUCAGGACAUGAGUCCUAUCUGUGGAGCUGCCCCCACAAUGGCUGGCUCUCCCACAACUGUGGCCAUCAUGAAGACGCUGGUGUCAUCUGCUCAGCUUCCCAGUCCCAGCCGACACCCAGCCCAGACACUUGGCCAACCUCACAUGCAUCAACAGCAGGAUCUGAAUCCAGUUUGGCCCUGAGGCUGGUGAAUGGAGGUGACAGGUGUCAGGGCCGAGUGGAGGUCCUAUACCGAGGCUCCUGGGGCACCGUGUGUGAUGACUACUGGGACACCAAUGAUGCCAAUGUGGUUUGCAGGCAGCUGGGCUGUGGCUGGGCCACGUCAGCCCCAGGAAAUGCCCGGUUUGGCCAGGGUUCAGGACCCAUUGUCCUGGAUGAUGUGCGCUGCUCAGGACAUGAGUCCUAUCUGUGGAGCUGCCCCCACAAUGGCUGGCUCUCCCACAACUGUGGCCAUCAUGAAGACGCUGGUGUCAUCUGCUCAGCUUCCCAGUCCCAGCCGACACCCAGCCCAGACACUUGGCCAACCUCACAUGCAUCAACAGCAGGAUCUGAAUCCAGUUUGGCCCUGAGGCUGGUGAAUGGAGGUGACAGGUGUCAGGGCCGAGUGGAGGUCCUAUACCGAGGCUCCUGGGGCACCGUGUGUGAUGACUACUGGGACACCAAUGAUGCCAAUGUGGUUUGCAGGCAGCUGGGCUGUGGCUGGGCCACGUCAGCCCCAGGAAAUGCCCGGUUUGGCCAGGGUUCAGGACCCAUUGUCCUGGAUGAUGUGCGCUGCUCAGGACAUGAGUCCUAUCUGUGGAGCUGCCCCCACAAUGGCUGGCUCUCCCACAACUGUGGCCAUCAUGAAGACGCUGGUGUCAUCUGCUCAGCUUCCCAGUCCCAGCCGACACCCAGCCCAGACACUUGGCCAACCUCUCGUGCAUCAACAGCAGGAUCUGAAUCCACUUUGGCCCUGAGACUGGUGAAUGGAGGUGACAGGUGUCGAGGCCGAGUGGAGGUCCUAUACCAAGGCUCCUGGGGCACCGUGUGUGAUGACUACUGGGACACCAAUGAUGCCAACGUGGUCUGCAGGCAGCUGGGCUGUGGCUGGGCCAUGUCAGCCCCAGGAAAUGCCCAGUUUGGCCAGGGCUCAGGACCCAUUGUCCUGGAUGAUGUGCGCUGCUCAGGACACGAGUCUUACCUGUGGAGCUGCCCCCACAAUGGCUGGCUCUCCCACAACUGUGGCCAUCAUGAAGAUGCUGGUGUCAUCUGCUCAGCUGCUCAGUCCCAGUCAACGCCCAGGCCAGAUACUUGGCUGACCACCAACUUACCGGCAUUGACAGUAGGAUCUGAAUCCAGUUUGGCUCUGAGGCUGGUGAAUGGAGGUGACAGGUGUCGAGGCCGAGUGGAGGUCCUGUAUCGAGGCUCCUGGGGAACCGUGUGUGAUGACAGCUGGGACACCAAUGAUGCCAAUGUGGUCUGCAGGCAGCUGGGCUGUGGCUGGGCCAUGUCGGCCCCAGGAAAUGCCCGGUUUGGCCAGGGCUCAGGACCCAUUGUCCUGGAUGAUGUGCGCUGCUCAGGGAAUGAGUCCUACCUGUGGAGCUGCCCCCACAAAGGCUGGCUCACCCACAACUGUGGCCAUCACGAAGACGCUGGUGUCAUCUGCUCAGCCACCCAAAUAAAUUCUACUACGACAGAUUGGUGGCAUCCAACAACUACAACCACUGCAAGACCCUCUUCAAAUUGUGGUGGCUUCUUAUUCUAUGCCAGUGGGACAUUCUCCAGCCCAUCCUACCCUGCAUACUACCCCAACAAUGCUAAGUGUGUUUGGGAAAUAGAAGUGAAUUCUGGUUAUCGCAUAAACCUGGGCUUCAGUAAUCUGAAAUUGGAGGCACACCAUAACUGCAGUUUUGAUUAUGUUGAAAUCUUUGAUGGAUCAUUGAAUAGCAGUCUCCUGCUGGGGAAAAUCUGUAAUGAUACCAGGCAAAUAUUUACAUCUUCUUACAACCGAAUGACCAUUCACUUUCGAAGUGACAUCAGUUUCCAAAACACUGGCUUUUUGGCUUGGUAUAACUCCUUCCCAAGCGAUGCCACCUUGAGGUUGGUCAAUUUAAAUUCAUCCUAUGGUCUAUGUGCCGGGCGUGUAGAAAUUUACCAUGGUGGCACCUGGGGGACAGUUUGUGAUGACUCCUGGACCAUUCAGGAAGCUGAGGUGGUCUGCAGACAGCUAGGGUGUGGACGUGCAGUUUCAGCCCUUGGAAAUGCAUAUUUUGGCUCUGGCUCUGGCCCCAUCACCCUGGACGAUGUAGAGUGCUCAGGGACGGAAUCCACUCUCUGGCAGUGCCGGAACCGAGGCUGGUUCUCCCACAACUGUAAUCAUCGUGAAGAUGCUGGUGUCAUCUGCUCAGGAAACCAUCUAUCGACACCUGCUCCUUUUCUCAACAUCACCCGUCCAAACACAGAUUAUUCCUGCGGAGGCUUCCUAUCCCAACCAUCAGGGGACUUUUCCAGCCCAUUCUAUCCCGGGAACUAUCCAAACAAUGCCAAGUGUGUGUGGGACAUUGAGGUGCAAAACAACUACCGUGUGACUGUGAUCUUCAGAGAUGUCCAGCUUGAAGGUGGCUGCAACUAUGAUUAUAUUGAAGUUUUCGAUGGCCCCUACCGCAGUUCCCCUCUCAUUGCUCGAGUUUGUGAUGGGGCCAGAGGCUCCUUCACUUCUUCCUCCAACUUCAUGUCCAUUCGCUUCAUCAGUGACCACAGCAUCACAAGGAGAGGGUUCCGGGCUGAGUACUACUCCAGUCCCUCCAAUGACAGCACCAACCUGCUCUGUCUGCCAAAUCACAUGCAAGCCAGUGUGAGCAGGAGCUAUCUCCAAUCCUUGGGCUUUUCUGCCAGUGACCUUGUCAUUUCCACCUGGAAUGGAUACUACGAGUGUCGGCCCCAGAUAACGCCGAACCUGGUGAUAUUCACAAUUCCCUACUCAGGCUGCGGCACCUUCAAGCAGGCAGACAAUGACACCAUCGACUAUUCCAACUUCCUCACAGCAGCUGUCUCAGGUGGCAUCAUCAAGAGGAGGACAGACCUCCGUAUUCACGUCAGCUGCAGAAUGCUUCAGAACACCUGGGUCGACACCAUGUACAUUGCUAAUGACACCAUCCACGUUGCUAAUAACACCAUCCAGGUCGAGGAAGUCCAGUAUGGCAAUUUUGACGUGAACAUUUCCUUUUAUACUUCCUCAUCUUUCUUGUAUCCUGUGACCAGCCGCCCUUACUACGUGGACCUGAACCAGGACUUGUACGUUCAGGCUGAAAUCCUCCAUUCUGAUGCUGUACUGACCUUGUUUGUGGACACCUGCGUGGCAUCACCAUACUCCAAUGACUUCACGUCUUUGACUUAUGAUCUAAUCCGGAGUGGAUGCGUGAGGGAUGACACCUACGGACCCUACUCCUCGCCAUCUCUUCGCAUUGCCCGCUUCCGGUUCAGGGCCUUCCACUUCCUGAACCGCUUCCCCUCCGUGUACCUGCGUUGUAAAAUGGUGGUGUGCAGAGCGUAUGACCCCUCUUCCCGCUGCUACCGAGGCUGUGUGUUGAGGUCGAAGAGGGAUGUGGGCUCCUACCAGGAAAAGGUGGACGUCGUCCUGGGUCCCAUCCAGCUGCAGACCCCCCCACGCCGAGAAGAGGAGCCUCGGUAGGUGGUCGCUCUCAGACCCCACUGUCCACCGGGGCGCAGACCCCUGACUCGGGGACUUGGGAUGUUCCUCUUGGUGUCAUAUUCCAACUCAGAUUGAGCCCUACAUUGUGCUGCACCUGGUCAUACGGAGUUGAAUCAGACCUGGUUCCCGCCUCCCCCAAGGCUCAUGGUCCUUGGAGGACCCGUUGCAGGGUGAGGUCAAGAGAGUUCUGACCUGGAUGGCCCAUAGACCUGACGUCCCAGAAUCCAUGCUUCUCAUCUGCAAAAUGAAAAUGUCAAUACUUACUUCUUAGCACUGUUGAGAGGGUUACUUACAUAAAGGAAUUUUGGUGAAACUGC